AGACGAGGCCUGAGGCGGCGGCGCGAGGCAGAACAUGUAAGACCGUGAGACUGCUGUUGACAAUUACUGUUGGGAAUGGAGCAGCUGACAUACCUGUUCCGGUUAGACGAGGAAGCAUAUGAAGGCCUGAACAUGCCGGGAGGAAGAAUGAGAGGCCCAAGCGCAGCACACACAGCCCUGUGGCCACCCGCGAAUUCCCGCACACACACGGCCCUGUGGCCACCCGUGAAUUCCCACACACACACGGCCCUGUGGCCACCCGUGAAUUCCCACACACACACGGCCCUGUGGCCACCCGCGAAUUCCCGCACGCACGUGGCCCUGUGGCCACGCAUGAAUUCCUGUACAGGAUUUUUCCGGAGCGUAGUCAGUUCCAGCUAUUCUUCAGAUGCUCUGGAUUUUGAGACGGAGCACAAAUUGGACCCUGUAUUUGAUUCUCCACGGAUGUCCCGCCGUAGUUUGCGCCUGGCCACGACAGCAUGCACCCUGGGGGAUGGUGAGGCUGUGGGUGCCGACAGCGGCACCAGCAGCGCUGUCUCCCUGAAGAACCGAGCGGCCAGAACAACAAAACAGCGCAGAAGCACAAACAAAUCAGCUUUUAGUAUCAACCACGUGUCAAGGCAGGUCACGUCCUCUGGCGUCAGCCACGGCGGCACUGUCAGCCUGCAGGAUGCUGUGACUCGACGGCCUCCUGUAUUGGACGAGUCUUGGAUUCGUGAACAGACCACAGUGGACCACUUCUGGGGUCUUGAUGAUGAUGGUGAUCUUAAAGGUGGAAAUAAAGCUGCCAUUCAGGGAAACGGGGAUGUGGGAGCCGCCGCCGCCACCGCGCACAACGGCUUCUCCUGCAGCAACUGCAGCAUGCUGUCCGAGCGCAAGGACGUGCUCACGGCGCACCCCGCGGCCCCCGGGCCCGUGUCGAGAGUUUAUUCUAGGGACAGGAAUCAAAAAUCUCAUGCCAGUUACUAUGGGAGAAUGAAUGUGAGAGAGGUUCUCAGAGAGGAUGGCCACCUCAGUGUAAAUGGGGAAGCGCUGUGCGACGACUGUAAGGGCAAGAGGCACCUCGACGCGCACACAGCCGCCCACUCGCAGUCGCCACGGCUGCCCGGUCGGGCAGGGACCCUCUGGCACAUCUGGGCAUGUGCAGGUUACUUCUUGCUGCAGAUUCUGCGCAGGAUCGGAGCUGUGGGCCAGGCUGUGUCCAGGACGGCGUGGUCGGCCCUUUGGCUGGCCGUGGUUGCUCCAGGGAAGGCAGCCUCUGGAGUGUUCUGGUGGCUGGGGAUUGGAUGGUACCAGUUUGUUACUUUGAUUUCUUGGCUGAAUGUGUUUCUUCUUACCAGGUGCCUUCGAAACAUCUGCAAGUUUUUAGUCUUGCUCAUCCCACUCUUCCUUUUACUAGCAGGUCUCUCCUUACGGGGCCAGGGCAAUUUCUUUUCGUUCUUGCCCGUGUUGAACUGGGCAAGCAUGCAUAGAACACAGCGGGUGGAUGACCCCCAGGACGUGUUUAAACCCACGACUUCUCGCCUGAAGCAGCCUCUGCAGGGUGACAGUGAGGCUUUUCCGUGGCAUUGGAUGAGUGGCGUGGAGCAGCAGGUGGCCUCUCUGUCUGGACAGUGCCACCACCAUGGUGAGAAUCUCCGAGAGCUGACCACUUUGCUACAGAAGCUGCAGGCUCGGGUGGACCAGAUGGAAGGCGGCGCUGCCGGGCCGUCAGCUUCGGUCAGAGACGCUGUGGGACAGCCCCCGAGGGAGACUGACUUUAUGGCCUUUCACCAAGAACAUGAAGUGCGUAUGUCACACUUGGAAGAUAUUCUGGGAAAACUGAGAGAAAAAUCUGAGGCCAUCCAGAAGGAACUAGAACAGACCAAGCAAAAAACAAUCAGUGCGGUUGGUGAGCAGCUCCUGCCCACAGUCGAGCACCUCCAGCUGGAGCUGGAUCAGCUAAAGUCAGAGCUGUCCAGCUGGCGACACGUGAAGACCGGCUGUGAGACAGUGGAUGCCGUACAAGAAAGAGUGGACGUGCAAGUCAGAGAAAUGGUGAAACUCCUGUUUUCCGAAGAUCAGCAAGGCGGUUCUCUGGAACAGCUGCUGCAGAGGUUCUCAUCACAGUUUGUGAGCAAAGGCGACUUGCAGACGAUGCUGCGAGACCUGCAGCUGCAGAUCCUGCGGAACGUCACCCACCACGUUUCCGUGACCAAGCAGCUCCCAACCUCAGAAGCCGUGGUGUCUGCUGUGAGCGAGGCGGGGGCGUCUGGAAUAACAGAGGCGCAAGCACGUGCCAUCGUGAACAGCGCCUUGAAGCUGUAUUCCCAAGAUAAGACCGGGAUGGUGGACUUUGCUCUGGAAUCUGGUGGUGGCAGCAUCUUGAGUACUCGCUGUUCUGAAACUUACGAAACCAAAACGGCGCUGAUGAGUCUGUUUGGGAUCCCGCUGUGGUACUUCUCGCAGUCCCCGCGCGUGGUCAUCCAGCCUGACAUUUACCCCGGUAACUGCUGGGCAUUUAAAGGCUCCCAGGGGUACCUGGUGGUGAGGCUCUCCAUGAUGAUCCACCCAGCCGCCUUCACUCUGGAGCACAUCCCUAAGACGCUGUCGCCAACAGGCAACAUCAGCAGCGCCCCCAAGGACUUCGCCGUCUAUGGAUUAGAAAAUGAGUAUCAGGAAGAAGGGCAGCUUCUGGGACAGUUCACGUAUGAUCAGGAUGGGGAGUCGCUCCAGAUGUUCCAGGCCCUGAAAAGACCCGACGACACAGCUUUCCAAAUAGUGGAACUUCGGAUUUUUUCUAACUGGGGCCAUCCUGAGUAUACCUGUCUGUAUCGGUUCAGAGUUCAUGGCGAACCUGUCAAGUGAAGACACUACUCAUUAUUUUUGUACAUUUUUGUAUAUACUGGGACAGCGUGAAACACUGGAAUCCUUCAUGGACGAGGGCAUAUACAAUGAUGGGACAGUGCCACACUCCUUCAAUAAACGUGGCUGCUGGCCAGAGGACGUGAGCGUGUGACGGGCGCCUUGGCGCCACCUGUUGGGUGCUCACUGCCUCUGCAGGUGCAGAGGGGUCAGCAGCAGGAGAAGCGUGUUGAACACGUGGCUCUCAGACACUCCUUGUUUUUAACGGGAAGCUCUUUGCAUUUGCAUUUCCUCAACAAAGGAGCAAAGCAGAGGAAGCUGAGAGUCUGGCGUGUUCUUGACGCUUUGGUCUUCAGCCUUGCACUGGCUCUUCUAAAGGACUUUUGGAGGGCAGAUAAUUUCAUCUGUUAAAUCCAACACACAUUUCUUUCAGGGAAAAACAAUGUCACCAAAUUUUCAGAGUUCUAAACUCCUUUCCUUCAAGCCGGAAUUUUCCUUUUUUCAGCACCAGUAGGUACUAAGUCUCCAGAUGGGGAAAUAACUAAAAUGUGUUUUUCUGCUUUGUUCGCUCUUACUUCUGAGGAAGGUUUCCAGUCAGGACUCGCUGUACCAAUAUCCAUGGAGGAAUAUGGGAGCGUUUCGCUCUCCUUGUAGGCUGAAGUCAGUCUGACUUGAAGGGGCCUGGUUUGGAUCUAAGCAAACACCCAGAUGGGGUUCUCUGGUCUCAGCAAGGCUUUUCCUGUUGGGAGUCACAGUAAACAGAAACCCAAAAAUCUCAUCUUGGGUGUUUUCAGGGCUUGUUUUGAGUUUUGCUGAAUAGGGAGCGCAAGACGCCCUGAGCCUCCCUCUCACUGGUGGUGAUAAGAGGAGCCGUCUGGUGUGUCAGGGUCACGAACCCGUUACAUUUCAGGACGAUCCUUUUUCCUUCAGCAGCAUUUCUUACUGGCUGUGGCUGGAAUCUGCCUUUUAUCACAGCUGUCACCAUUCUCACGUGAUUCUUGUGAGACUCUUUUUGGUUAUAAUUACUAUUUAAUAUUUAGACUAUUUUACUGAGCAGACUUUAUAAAUGAGAUAUCUACAAGGCACUUAAAGUGUUACAGAUGUUUUACCUUAAGAAUUAUUUAAGUUGUGUUGGGUUAAGACAGUUUUCAGUGUACCGUAAAUGUUGUGUUUUCAGAAAAAGACAAAACGAUGGUGCUGACUGGUUUUCUGUAUAUUGCACAACAGUCCUCAAAUACACUGAUGUAUGAAACUAUUCAUACAUCAAGCAGCAUUUUUUUCACUCUCCUUAGAAUUGGAACUAUGCAGUUAAGGCAGAUAAAAUGUACAGAUGUUUCAUAUAUUACAGGUUACAUAUAUAAAUCAAAAUUUCCUAUAUAAAACUGAUUUGGGAUUUGGGGUGGAAAUAUUUUGAAUAUUAAUUUAUUUUUAAAGAUGCAAGAUAGGACUUUGUGCAAUGUAUUUUUGUAAAUGCUUUUCAAAAUAUCUGUCUUUGGUAGUGCUUCUGCUGCUGCCACCAAAUUGAUAAGAUGCUAUUAAGAGGUUUAAAUAAAGAGUUUUAAUUUUUAAAAGGGCAUGGGAUAUAAACAGUCUAUUUCUUUUCUCA